AGUUGAGCUGAACGGAGUCCACACAGGCAGACUUGACCUUGACCAGAUAGUCUUCAAGAUGCCAAACUGGGGCGGAGGCGCAAAAUGUGGAGCCUGUGAAAAGACCGUCUACCAUGCAGAAGAAAUCCAGUGCAAUGGAAGGAGUUUCCACAAGACGUGUUUCCACUGCAUGGCCUGCAGGAAGGCUCUUGACAGCACGACAGUCGCGGCUCAUGAGUCGGAGAUCUACUGCAAGGUGUGCUAUGGGCGCAGAUAUGGCCCCAAAGGGAUCGGGUAUGGACAAGGCGCUGGCUGUCUCAGCACAGACACGGGCGAGCAUCUCGGCCUGCAGUUCCAACAGUCCCCAAAGCCGGCACGCUCAGUUACCACCAGCAACCCUUCCAAAUUCACUGCGAAGUUUGGAGAGUCCGAGAAGUGCCCUCGAUGUGGCAAGUCAGUCUAUGCUGCUGAGAAGGUUAUGGGAGGUGGCAAGCCUUGGCACAAGACCUGUUUCCGCUGUGCCAUCUGUGGGAAGAGUCUGGAGUCCACAAAUGUCACUGACAAAGAUGGGGAACUUUAUUGCAAAGUUUGCUAUGCCAAAAAUUUUGGCCCCACGGGUAUUGGGUUUGGAGGCCUUACACAACAAGUGGAAAAGAAAGAAUGAAGAGGUGCGCCGUUUCUCAGAUUUUUUGCGAGCCUAAAACACUUGCCAAGUAAUCCUGCACAGAUCGAUACCUUUCCCCAAAUAGCCUCUCCUUUGUAGUCGUACAUUAUGUGUUUCUCCUCAGAAGUGAUCAGGUCUUUACUGAAUGUUAGAAGAGGCCUUUGGAAGAAAAUUAUGUAAAGUUUAAUCUAUAACAAAUGCUUUAUUAUUUAUAAUGCUUGGAAUGGGAGAGGCAAUAAAUAAAUGUUUUAGUGCUAUCUUGUAUGGCUCUAGAUCUUUUCUUUGAGAUAGAAAUUUUCAAAAACAUAAAGCUAGUUCAAAAAACGAGUUGCAGAGCAUAUAAUAAAUUUGGAUGUCAACUGAGAAAGGAGUGAGAAGGAAGAAACAAUGCGCAAAGGAAAGCAGUCUUUCAGAAUCUGUCAGCCAAGUGUCUUUCUAGUUACUGCUAAUGGAGAAGAAAACAGGGGGUCUGGGAGAAAAUAGAGAACAUGAUAGCAAAAUCUAAAAGGAAAAUCAAAACUAAUAAAAUUGCUGAAGAGUUGAUCCCUUUGUCCUAUCGUGGGGCUUUGUAAUGUUACACAUCUCGUGAAAACUCAGAAAUGACAAUAAAGCGUGGCAUUUGCCUCUGUAUUAUAAAUGA